ACAAACCAAAAAAAACCCCAUGAUACAAUGAUUCAAACAAAAACUGUGCCAUCAGCUUUUACAUGAGGCCAGGGCCACCUGAGUCACCUCGUGGACCAAUACCUGCCCGCUGGCUCGUCUUUCCCAGGCCCACUUUGGAGGUGGGUGCUUUCCUUCUGGCCUCCAGUUUCCAUCUGCUGCCCCUCAGAUAGGUCUCUUUGUGCCAUCUCUUUCCACGCGGGCAGUUUUUUAUUACUUUUCUGGGGCACAGAAAUAUGUGUAUUUCUAUUUCUUUUUAUAACCCAGGACCAUGUUGUAGAACUCUGCUUGGGCAAAGCACCAUUGGCGUAUUAGACAUUCUGGGGAACUAUCUGUAGGUAUCUGUAAACAAAUUGCACUUCCUGCUGUCAUGAGAAGGGGCUCACCAUCAGUUCCAUUCCUAUUUUUUUCUGUUUUAGAUGUCGGUCCCAGGAAACCAUUUUCACAUAGAGGAGCAGGUGGGACUGGAGUUUCUGAGUGCUGGGGUCCCUGGAGCCUUCUGCAGUGUCCUGGGAGGGGUGACUGGGAAAGGCCAGGGGGCAAGAGCUGCUAGGGGCCUUCUCAGAUUUCCCAGUUUUUACACAGAGUAUAUAUGGGAGUUGAGGUCUGGAAAAAUGAUUUUUUAAAAACUCUUCCUGCCCCGUGGACUCUCUUGAAGACGUCGUGUCAUGCCAGGGCCCACGGUCACUUGACGGAACCCUUGUGAUGCUGGCCACAACCUCAUGGGACUGGAUGGCGAGCAGCGAGGGGGGUCCAGUAACUGUUGGAUGCAGGAUUGAAUUCGGUCACCCGCACUUAUUUCCUGGGCUCGUCUUGGUUGGGUUCGCGGAGAUACACUCUCUGGGAGCGGACGCUUUGGUGAGGAAGACCAGGCGAAGAAGACAUGCUGCUGCUGAAGAAACACACGGAGGACAUCAGCAGCGUCUACGAGAUCCGCGAGAGGCUCGGCUCGGGUGCCUUCUCCGAGGUGGUGCUGGCCCAGGAGCGGGGCUCCGCACACCUCGUGGCCCUCAAGUGCAUCCCCAAGAAGGCCCUCCGGGGCAAGGAGGCCCUGGUGGAGAACGAGAUCGCAGUGCUCCGUAGGAUCAGUCACCCCAACAUCGUCGCUCUGGAGGAUGUCCACGAGAGCCCUUCCCACCUCUACCUGGCCAUGGAACUGGUGACGGGUGGCGAGCUGUUUGACCGCAUCAUGGAGCGCGGCUCCUACACAGAGAAGGAUGCCAGCCAUCUGGUGGGUCAGGUCCUUGGCGCCGUCUCCUACCUGCACAGCCUGGGGAUCGUGCACCGGGACCUCAAGCCCGAAAACCUCCUGUAUGCCACGCCCUUUGAGGACUCGAAGAUCAUGGUCUCUGACUUUGGACUCUCCAAAAUCCAGGCUGGGAACAUGCUAGGCACCGCCUGUGGGACCCCUGGAUAUGUGGCCCCAGAGCUCUUGGAGCAGAAACCCUACGGGAAGGCCGUAGAUGUGUGGGCCCUGGGCGUCAUCUCCUACAUCCUGCUGUGUGGGUACCCCCCCUUCUACGACGAGAGCGACCCUGAGCUCUUCAGCCAGAUCCUGAGGGCCAGCUAUGAGUUUGACUCUCCUUUCUGGGAUGACAUCUCAGAAUCAGCCAAAGACUUCAUCCGGCACCUUCUGGAGCGAGACCCCCAGAAGAGGUUCACCUGCCAACAGGCCUUGCGGCACCUUUGGAUCUCUGGGGACACAGCCUUCGACAGGGACAUCUUAGGCUCUGUCAGUGAGCAGAUCCGGAAGAACUUUGCUCGGACACACUGGAAGCGAGCCUUCAAUGCCACCUCGUUCCUGCGCCACAUCCGGAAGCUGGGGCAGAUCCCAGAGGGCGAGGGGGCCUCUGAGCAGGGCAUGGCCCGCCACAGCCACUCAGGCCUCCGUGCUGGCCAGCCCCCCAAGUGGUGAUGCCCAGGCAGAUGCCGAGGCCAAGUGGACUGACCCCCAGAUUUCCUUCCCUUGGAUGCUUUCGGUCCCCUCCCCCAACCCCUCCCCCUGGGGCUGGCCUCUGCUGGAUUUUGAGAUUUGAGGGUGUGGCGCAUGGCGCUGGGGUUGGAAUGGGGCACCCCCAAGUCUGUCCCCAGGCUCUGCCCUGCCUGGGGGCAGUGGCUCCCCUCCCCUGUUGCCUCUCCCGCCCCUGCCCCCCCCGCCCCGCCAAAAGCCGAGGGGGUGCUGGCAGGCGGGCCUCAGGGGCUGUCUUUCCUGCACGGCUGUUGUGUGCUUCGCUGAGUGUGGGUGGUCCUGCUUGUGUCAUGGUCAUGGCCUUCCAGCCCCCUCCAGUUUUCCCCAAACCAAUAAAGAAAGAUACAGCAA